CUCCUCCCCCUCCCGGCCAAGAUGUCUGACAUGGAGGAUGAUUUCAUGUGCGAUGAUGAGGAGGACUACGACCUGGAAUACUCUGAAGAUAGUAACUCCGAGCCAAAUGUGGAUUUGGAAAAUCAGUACUAUAAUUCCAAAGCAUUAAAAGAAGAUGACCCAAAAGCGGCAUUAAGCAGUUUCCAAAAGGUUUUGGAACUUGAAGGUGAAAAAGGAGAAUGGGGAUUUAAAGCACUGAAACAAAUGAUUAAGAUUAACUUCAAGUUGACAAACUUUCCAGAAAUGAUGAAUAGAUAUAAGCAGCUAUUGACCUAUAUUCGGAGUGCAGUCACAAGAAAUUAUUCUGAAAAAUCCAUUAAUUCUAUUCUUGAUUAUAUCUCUACUUCUAAACAGAAUUCUGAUUUUUUAUGUCAGAUGGAUUUACUGCAGGAAUUCUAUGAAACAACACUGGAAGCUUUGAAAGAUGCUAAGAAUGAUAGACUGUGGUUUAAGACAAACACAAAGCUUGGAAAAUUAUAUUUAGAACGAGAGGAAUAUGGAAAGCUUCAAAAAAUUUUACGCCAGUUACAUCAGUCGUGCCAGACUGAUGAUGGAGAAGAUGAUCUGAAAAAAGGUACACAGUUAUUAGAAAUAUAUGCUUUGGAAAUUCAAAUGUACACAGCACAGAAAAAUAACAAAAAACUUAAAGCACUCUAUGAACAGUCACUUCACAUCAAGUCUGCCAUCCCUCAUCCACUGAUUAUGGGAGUUAUCAGAGAAUGUGGUGGUAAAAUGCACUUGAGGGAAGGUGAAUUUGAAAAGGCACACACUGAUUUUUUUGAAGCCUUCAAGAAUUAUGAUGAAUCUGGAAGUCCAAGACGAACCACUUGCUUAAAAUAUUUGGUCUUAGCAAAUAUGCUUAUGAAAUCGGGAAUAAAUCCAUUUGACUCACAGGAGGCCAAGCCGUACAAAAAUGAUCCAGAAAUUUUAGCAAUGACGAAUUUAGUAAGUGCCUAUCAGAAUAAUGACAUCACUGAAUUUGAAAAGAUUCUAAAAACAAAUCACAGCAACAUCAUGGAUGAUCCUUUCAUAAGAGAACACAUUGAAGAGCUUUUGCGAAACAUCAGAACACAAGUGCUUAUAAAAUUAAUUAAGCCUUACACAAGAAUACAUAUUCCUUUUAUUUCUAAGGAGUUAAACAUAGAUGUAGCUGAUGUGGAGAGCUUGCUGGUGCAGUGCAUAUUGGAUAACACUAUUCAUGGCCGAAUUGAUCAAGUCAACCAACUCCUUGAACUGGAUCAUCAGAAGAGGGGUGGUGCACGAUAUACUGCACUAGAUAAAUGGACCAACCAACUAAAUUCUCUCAACCAGGCUGUAGUCAGUAAACUGGCUUAACAGAGAACAAGCUUUUACAGACGUCCUUAAGGCAACAGUGCAGAGAUGUAAUCCUUAAAAGAACUGGGAAUGGCAAAACUACUGUCGGUUGAUGUGUCCUGAAAAUUAUUGGAGUUAUGGCAGAAGUGCUUUUUUGAUCAACUGGUUUGUGUUUUGCUGCUGCAUUUAUCCCAAGAAAAACAGCUUUAAUCUCCAGAAGAAAACCAAAAUACCAUGGGAUUUAUGCUGUAUUGACAUCUUGCCCUAAACGUACAACAUCAUAGUAAUUUGUCAUGGGCAACAUGACCAGAGAGAAGAUUUUUGUCAUGAUUUUAAAUACACUGACACGCUACUGUUGGUUAAAUUUAAACAUGUUUUACCUGCAGAAAUUCUCUCACAAAUAACCUGCAAUAACUUGAAAUGCAUACCCUUUUGAACACUUCCUUUUCUCAUGUAUAAAUUAAAAUGUUUGCUGCAUUUUGCAAAAUGUCAAUUCUCUAAAAAUGUGUCCGUAUAUUUCUGUACCUGCAGUGUAGUAAAGGUUUAGACGAAACCCCAUAAUUAUAGUGGCAUACUGUCACUUAGGUUUCAAGCAGCAAAAUAAACAGUGCAGCUCAGAAAUUGUAGUUUGGUUCUUGAUGUGUUUUUAUUACAUUUGGAGUUGUUUUGUUUUUUAGUACCUUCGAAAUUUCAAAUUAUUUUAUCUUCAGUUAAUGAUUUUAAAAAGCCUGGGGGCAAAUAAGUUGGUUAUUUGCUUUCAAGUUUUUAAAAGUAGUCUUUAUUGAUAGAGUAAGGAGAACUACUUUCUAACAAAACACGUGCAUAGUUAUGACAGUGAUGCUUUAAAGGAAUAAAAUUCUUUUUUUUUAAAGAGUGAUAUUCCUUUUCAAAAGAAUACUAACUCUCAGAAUGUUCACUUUAAACGAAUAUGCCAGAACAUAGACAGCUAAAUGAAUGUUACUCUGCAUAGUGAUCAUGCUGGAAGGUUAUUUCCUAAUGCCAGCAAUCUACCAUUGCCCAAAACCUGCUGAGUUUACUCUUUUAGAAUUGCAUUCAAAGUUAAUUUGUCACACACACUAAACUUUAUGAUUAUACAUUGUUUUAAAAAAUAUAGUAUUAGGAAGCUUGAUUAUUUUUAGUUACCAUUACUUGGCACCAAAUGAAAGUUUCCAAAACUUCCACCUAACUUUGAGGUAAUGCAGAAAGUAUAUAACUGGCUUUGAAGGCAAUCCCAAAAGAGUUUUAAAGGUUUUUUGAGCAGUGGCAGUAUACUUAGGAGAAUGAACUGUGGCCUUCCAAGGUAACUACCUUAAAGGAACUCAGCUCAUUUGAAUGUAUUGAGUUUUGGAUGUAUUUGUUUCAUUUUUUAAAAAGUUCACAUUAUUUUAUAGUGUCGAAAGGAAGAACUAGGAUUAACAUAAUUUCUUUGGUUUUUCUAUUGCUUGUUAUUAUUAUGUAAAAACUGGGUGGCAGUUCAGAAGGAAGAUUGUGGUUACAGAAGAGUGACAACCAAGAAUUUUUUGAUCAUUAAAUCAGAUUUUAUAAACAGUGGAAGGAGCAUGGACUUAAAACAAGGCAUGCUUAUUCGGUUUUGUCAAAAUUUUACGAAAAUAUGUGAUAUAUAUUUAUACUAAAAAUAUAUAAUCCUUAGAUUUAGAAAAGCAAUCAGUUAAUGUCUUUAGCAGACUAAAGCAGUAUUAAACACAGGUACAAGUUGGAAAUUGUAGAAAACGGAAAGAAAACAAAAGACAAAAUGUCUAUGGUAGGGAAUAAAAGUUUAAGAUAUUAUAAAAUUAUGUGUAUUUUCUCUUUUACAUAAAUCAUUUGUGAAAAGUGUGCUAAACUUUUUUUACAAGAGUGAUAUUAAUUAGGAUUUAUUUUUCAAUAUAAUUUGGAGACCCUUUGUUAUCCAAAUAAAAAUGAUGAGUUUUUGUGCCUGUAUUCAAAUAUGUAUGCAUGUGAUAACCCUUGAAAGCUAAAGCCCUUCUUAACUUUUGAGUUGAUGGAAUUAGAAUUCAAAGAUUUGAAUGAAAUGAUUUAACCUUUAUCCUCCAAUUCUUACAGUGCCCAGUUCUCCUGUGCUAUCUUUGCUUUGUACAAUAGUGCAUCUUCCACUUUCUAGAGAGAAAGCAUGCACUUGUUAUUUGGAAAACUGGGCUAAAUAUAUAACAGUAUCCAAAGUUAUACCAUAAUAAUUUAUUGUAAUUGUGUAUUACAUAGCUUUGUUUACCCAGAUAUAGGUGCGUUCUUUUUUUUCUGUUAGUCAUCUGUGACUUUUGUUCUGGAAUACAGGUUUUUAAAUAUAUCUUAACAGUCUGACUAACUUAAAAUAAUUUAUUCUUCCCUUAAAACAUUUUUCUGUGUUUUUGUGCAUCAAAUAUUGUAGAGUUGAAAUCUUAGAGAUUGCUUAUCGAAAUAUAAAUUUAGGGGAAGUUAAAAAUCGAUUGGCAAAUUUGUAGCAUUUAUUCACUGAUUAAAUCUUUUCCACUUUUGUGAAAACCAUACCAGUGGUUUACAUCAUAUUGUAAUGUGUUCAUCUCAUUCUUCUUUUUAUCCCUAAACCUAGCUAAAAGUUACUGCAAAGAAAUCUUUGGCUGCCACAAGUAGAUGCUCUCUACUACAAGAGCUGGAUUUCCAUUACUCACUCUUGCUCUUACAUUAAAGUUGUUGAUUAAAUACUUUUUCUCUACAUCUUAAUGUAACAUAACUGAUUUCUUUUUAAAGAUGAGUAUAUAUGUACUAAGUAAUGCUCUCAUUACAUGAGUCCCUUCUAACUACAGGCUGAUACAUCUUUCAGGAAAACUGAGAACCUAAUAUUUAAGUGAGGCCUAUUUUAAAUGAGCUAUACUGUGGGUGGUAGUGUUUGUUACCUUAUGUAAGACUUAGGUUUGUCUUAGACUGAAAAACUCUUAUUCUUAAUAUUUAAAAUAUCCAUGAUGGUAGAAAUUUUGUGGGAAAUUUUCUUUUUUAAUCAAUAGUUACAGUUCUUCAGUAAACACAGGUAUGUAUGCUUUUGUGGUGUCAGUGUCAGUCUAAAUCUAUGGGUGAAGCAGUUAGUCCAUAAGACAAAAAAUUAUUUGCCUAGUGGAUUCCCUUUACCUCUUUUUAAGAAGCUCAGAGAUCUGUAAUCAUUAAUUUACUAAGGAUUUUUUAAAAUAUUAUUUUAGUCACUUUUAAACCUGAAAAUUUCUCUUUUGAUUUAGAUUUUUGAAGUGAGGCUUGAGCAUACACAAGUAAAGCUGGGAGUUUCAUUCUUCAUAUGGGAUUUAUGACUAAAUAUUUCUAGCAUUUUGAAGAAGAUAAACAUUUUGAACUGAAGUAUAUAACAAAAAAAGGAAUUUGACAUUUAACUAUUUUGUAUCAAAGUGUUUAAGAACACUAUCCAGAACAAGAGAUGGAGUAUCAGGUUUCAGAAUGUGACGCAAAAGGCAUUUGGUCUUCAUUUAUGUGACCACAAUUAAAAUUUUCCUCUUUUUUUCUUUUUCUGGAGGUUUUCUUUUAGUUUUCAUUGUUUUAGGUUUUUUUUUCCCCCAAAUCAGCAUCCUAUUUAUAUUUGUUUGAUACGGUUUUUUUGUUUUUGUUUUUGUUUUGCUUUUUUUGGAAACAGUUUCGCUCUUGUCACCCAGGCUGGAGUGCAGUGGCGCAAUCUCAGUUCACUGCCACCUCCACCUCCCGGGUUCAAGCGAUUCUCCUGCCUCAAUCUCCGGAGUAGCUGGGAUUACAGACACCCGCCACCACGCCCAGCUAAUUUUUGUGUUUUUAGUAGAGACAAGAUUUCACCAUGUUGGCCAGGCUGGUCUCAAACUCCUGACCUCAGGCGAUCCACCGCUUUGGCCUCCCAUAGUGCUGGGAUUACAGGCGUGAGCCACCACGCCCAGCCUGAUACAGUUUUAAGCAGGAAUUUGGCAGAAAUUUCGUAACGAAGACAAAUUGGAGGUUCUCUUUAACUCGAGAUUAUUAAAUUUAUAGUAACUUCUUGGGCCAUUAAAAUGUGAGUUUAAAUGCCAUUUGGAGGAUUUGUGUUAUAUUAAGCACCACAAAUUUAAACUGUCAACUAGUGAUUCUACAUGUUUCUCAAAAUGCUAAAGUUUAGCAUCACUUACUUGCUUUUGAAUUUUAAGGAGAUUCGUCUUAGGUAAUGUCUCAGAAGAAACCAGUGUGUGGUUCUCUAAAAUUUUACUUUUUUACUGUCACGUAUAAUAAUAUCUAAACUACCUGUAGUAGUUAAAAAUAUUACGGCAUCAAAGGUAUAUGCCAAGUGUACCUUAAAACCCUGUGACAGGAAAAAAGAAAAAAUUAUUUCUUAAGUACUUACUAUUCGGGGGCAACUUUGUUCCGUGUUGGCAAAAUUAUGAACUUUGCUCAGAAUUUCCACAUGAAUAGCUGACCAAAACUUUUUUGUGUGCAUAUGUAUACAUAUGUAAUAAGUGAAACAUACUUGUGGGAGUACAAAAUUCAUCACCAGUUUAUCACAGUAAUUUUCCAGUUUUCUAUUUUACUUAAUAUCACUUAUUUCUGACACAGGCAAAUGUCAUAUGCCAUGAAAAGAAUUACCAGUGUACCAGUAACUUGCGUGUUAUGACUAGGUUUCAUGUGGAAGACUGUCCAAAUUUACAUAAUCUAGAGUAAUUUUUUAAUUCUGAAGUAAGGGCAUUUUAAAAUUAAUUGCUAAAGGUUGUUUUAUUGUACAUCCAUUUUAUGGGAGUUUAGAGUUUAGAAAAAGUAAUCUCUAGCGUCAUCCCAUGAAGUUGUCAAAAGUUUUGGCAUGCUUAUUAGCAACAUAUUAAUGCCAAGUGUUGAGUAUCUAAUUUCUGUUCAAAUGUUUGCCUAUCCCUUACUGUUUACGACAGUAAUAAAUUUUUAUGCAUCUAUUUUAAAUAACACUGAAGAAAAUUAAAAUAUAUUUCAAGAAAUGGAGCAAUGACAUGGAAAAUAGAAAGUUGUUUGGUUUUGCAAUGUGUUACAUAAUUGGUUGCAUUAUAAAUUUUCUCCAUUUUGUUUAUGAUAAGCUAAUAUAAAAGGUAUCAAAUUCCUUGAGCUAACACUAGGUGGGAAGGAAGUAGUAGGUGAUUAGGAAUGUAACAGGAUGUCUGCCUGAAAUGGUCAGUUCCACCAAUUAAUAAUUGAGAACUGAUUAUAUGUGCAGGAUGUGUCAUAAGAUGCUGUAAGGCUUAAAUACUCAAGGGUUUUUUUAUUUAUCUGGAAGUGCACAUUCCUUAUUGGUAAUAAAAAAUACGUAAUCUA